GCGCUGGUGUGGGUUAGGGCUGAGAAAGAACGACAGGAACAGAGACGUCGCGAGGAUUAAGUUUAAGACUUCGCGAGAACAGAAUUUCUUUUGGCACCUCCUCUCCGCGCGUUCUUGGGGUGAGGCUGGGUAAUUGUUCCUGCAGGGUGGUGGGUGAUAGUGGCCAGUUGACUGCGACUGUGUUUGGGUGGUGGGAAGCCUGAAGAAAAGGUUGUUUCUUACCGGUCGCUGCCUCAGGGAGGUAGUGCGGUAGAAUUUUCCGCUAUGGGUCAUUCUCGGUGUCCGCGGGGAAGGGCGUGACAACGACGGGCGUGACGGCGAAGCAACAGUGUCUCGAGAGCGCUGCCGCCCGGAGGGCGCCAGGAGAAGUGCGUCCGAGACGCCGCGCGGUGAUGCUCCUGAAAACGUCUGCCCGGCGUAGCGGGAACCCAGCAUGAUUUUCAGGAGUCUCUGUUGCCCAGGCUGGAAUGCAAUGGUGCGAUCUCAGUCACUACAACCUCUGCCUCCCGGGUUCAAGCGAUUAUCCUGCUUCAGCCUCCCGAGUAGCUGGAAUUACAGGGUUGAAAGGAGGAGCAGGAGGUACUGAUGGACAAGGAGGUACCUUCCGGUACACCUUUCAUGGCGAUCCUCAUGCUACAUUUGCUGCAUUUUUCGGAGGGUCCAACCCCUUUGAAAUUUUCUUUGGAAGACGAAUGGGUGGUGGUAGAGAUUCUGAAGAAAUGGAAAUAGAUGGUGAUCCUUUUAGUGCCUUUGGUUUCAGCAUGAAUGGAUAUCCAAGAGACAGGAAUUCUGUGGGGCCAUCCCGCCUCAAACAAGAUCCUCCAGUUAUUCAUGAACUUAGAGUAUCACUUGAAGAGAUAUAUAGUGGUUGUACCAAACGGAUGAAGAUUUCUCGAAAAAGGCUAAACGCUGAUGGAAGGAGUUACAGAUCUGAGGACAAAAUUCUUACCAUUGAGAUUAAAAAAGGGUGGAAAGAAGGCACCAAAAUUACUUUUCCAAGAGAAGGAGAUGAAACACCAAAUAGUAUUCCAGCAGACAUUGUUUUUAUCAUUAAAGACAAAGAUCAUCCAAAAUUUAAAAGGGAUGGAUCAAAUAUAAUUUAUACUGCUAAAAUUAGUUUACGAGAGGCAUUGUGUGGCUGCUCAAUUAAUGUACCAACACUGGAUGGAAGAAACAUACCUAUGUCAGUAAAUGAUAUUGUGAAACCCGGAAUGAGGAGAAGAAUUAUUGGAUAUGGGCUGCCAUUUCCAAAAAAUCCUGACCAACGUGGUGACCUUCUAAUAGAAUUUGAGGUGUCCUUCCCAGAUACUAUAUCUUCUUCAUCCAAAGAAGUACUUAGGAAACAUCUUCCUGCCUCAUAGAAUGAAGAACUUUGUUACACAUAUUUUGAUAAGGCACUGAAAAUAUAAAAGGACUGGUAGUUUACUGAUGUAGAUGUGAAUUCUGUAUAAAGAUGUGUAAAUUCUUUUGAGGGUUCAUUAAAUUGCAUGAAUAGAGACGGGUCAAAUAAAUAGGCAAAAGGGAUUUUUACAGUUAGAGAUAAAAGAGAAAACCAUUCACUGUAUUUUAUUUCAUUUCUCCUGAUUCAGAUAUUUUUAGUAAUUUGCUUAUAUGUAAAAGUUGUUUUUGUGGAGUCAGUGGAUAUAUUUCUAAUGAAGUGCUAGACUAUCCAAUUACUUAAUUUCUUAUACCUUUAGAUAAUCAGUAUGAAAAGUUCCCAUUUAUAAUGGAAAUGAAAAUUCUUAACUAAACUAUACAUGUAAUAUGUAUUUCUAGAAGAGAAUAAAAACCCAAGUCAGUUAUUAGAUUUAAAUCACCUUCUGAAAUGCUGCUAUAGGGCUGGUAUCUGUAAAAGAAUAUCCUGAUGCAUCUGUUUCACCAUUUUGAUUUUUAAAGUAUGCUGUAGCAUUUCUUAAUAACAUCGUUGUGAUGUUCUUAAGGCAGAUCUUUCUUCAUAAAAAGGAAAGUAAUGGCAAUUUCUCUCCUGUGGAAAUCCCAAUUGCUUGAAUUACUGAUAUUUUAGAAUAGACUUUUUAAAAUGCCAUAUGUAAUUUUAUGCAAGUUGACUAUAUAUCUUGUACUUAAUAAAUUAUAGGCUCAUUUUGUUCUCUGCUAGUUUAAAGUAAUUCGUUUAAUAAUAGAUGUGUUUUUAGAGGAAAUGCUGUUACUUGGAAUUAAUUUUCCAGUUAUACAGUCUUCUAUAACUUACUAAUAAUAUUCUAUAUGUACUUUAUGUAAUUUCCCUAAAAAGAAUGAACUACCACUACACUAUGGUGUUAAACCAAAAUAUAGGGAAAAUAAACACUAACUGCUGCUUAUGGAUAAUGUUGCAACUACUUGUUAUGCAUAUAAAUAUUUUACUUUUUCACAUGUAUAGAUUGCAUUUCUUAGGUGUUUUAAUUUUUUAAAUAUAUUUAUGUUUUAAAAAUUUAGUUUUGUUUUCUGUUUUAUAACUAUAGUGAGAAUGAUGUUUUGAAGCAAAAUUUUUGGUUAUAAAAUAGUUUUCAGGAUUAUAUAUAUAUAUACUGGAUCCUAUCGCCUUUUAGUAGAAUAUGAAAUAUUCUUUUAGAAAUCCAAUAUAAAUAGGUUAUAAUAGCCAUAUUCUUUAUUACUUUAUUGAGAUAUAAUUUACAUGCCAUAAAGUUUACCCUUAAAAUAUAUAAUUCAGUGGUUUUUAGUGAUAUUUACAAAGUGGUACAAUCAUCAUCACUUUCUAAUUCCAGAAUAUUUUCAUCACCCCAAAAAGAAAUCCUAAAUCCAUUAGCAGUUACUUCCCAUUCUUCCCUUCCUCCAGCCCCUGAAAACACUACCAUCUACUUUUCAUCUGUAUGGAUUUGUCUGUUCUGGACAUUUCACAUAAAUAGACUCAAACAAUAUAUGGCUUUUUUUUUUUUUGGUCUGGCCUCUUUCAUUUAGCUUAAUGUUUUCAAGGUUCAUCUAUGUUGUAUCACGUAUCAGUACUUUAUUUUUUGUGUGGCACGUCAUAUGGAUAUACCACAAUUUGUUUAUCUUUUCAUUAAUUAUGGGCAUUUGGCUUAUUUCUACUUUUUUGGCUAUUAUAAAUAAUGCUGCUGUGAA